GGGGUCCAAUUUGUGCGCGUGGAGUGAGACAGAAAACCUGGAGCCCGAUCUCCCGGCCAGCGACUCCCUCCUUCUGGGUGUGCGGCUGAAGACUGGAAGCAGGUUGCCUUGCCUGCUGCAAGCCCGCCGUACCUACCCCUUCUCCGCGUGCGCCCCUCCCUGUGCCUGCGCAUUACCGGCUAGCCGGCGGCGGGCGCUGCAGCCCCUACGUGAUUCUGCGGCUCACUCCCCUCGGAUGGUCUUUCCACCCGAGUUUUUCCCGGGAAGAGGCUCUCAAGACUAGCCAGUGCAGGAGGAGGAGUCGAACUCUGGAUAGCCUGUUUAUAAAGCCCUAACUGUGCCGAUGUUGACCGUUUUCUGAAACUCCUCCUCCAAAACCCACGCCAAACCACAAGAUGAAGGAAAUUCACACAUCAGGAUGCCAAAAACCAUGGAAGACUUCUGAUGUUCUGGGAGGGUUGACAAAGAUGGACCUUAAAUUCUAGAAUUUAGGUAUUCAUGGUUGAGAUCCUGAAGAAAACAUUUUCUGCUGAGCAGAAGCAAUUUAAUAAUUGCCUCCCUUCAUUCAUAUUUCCUUCACAAACAGAAAAUGAAUGAAAAUAAAGAUACUGAUUCAAAGAAAAGUGAAGAAUACGAAGAUGACUUUGAAAAGGACCUGGAGUGGUUAAUUAAUGAAAAUGAAAAAAGUGAUGCCAGCAUAAUAGAGAUGGCUUGUGAGAAGGAAGAGAAUAUUAACCAAGACUUAAAAGAGAAUGAGACAGUAAUGGAGCACACCAAACGGCAUUCUGAUCCUGACAAAUCUUUGCAGGAUGAGGUCUCACCAAGAAGAAAUGACAUCAUUUCUGUACCAGGUAUUCAACCUUUGGAUCCCAUAUCAGAUUCAGAUAGUGAAAACUCUUUCCAGGAAUCCAAACUAGAAAGCCAGAAAGACUUGGAGGAGGAAGAGGAUGAGGAAGUAAGGAGAUAUAUUAUGGAGAAAAUUGUACAAGCUAACAAGCUUCUACAGAAUCAAGAACCGGUGAAUGAUAAAAGGGAGCGAAAACUUAAGUUCAAGGACCAGUUAGUUGAUUUGGAAGUUCCUCCACUAGAAGACACUACUACUUUUAAAAAUUAUUUUGAAAACGAAAGGAAUAUGUUUGGGAAACUGUCACAAUUAUGUAUUUCCAAUGAUUUUGGACAAGAAGAUGUGCUCCUGUCACUUACUAAUGGAAGCUGUGAAGAAAACAAGGAUAGGACAAUACUGGUAGAGAGAGAUGGAAAAUUUGAACUUCUGAAUUUACAAGACAUUGCCAGUCAGGGGUUUUUGCCUCCCAUUAAUAAUGCAAAUAGUACAGAAAAUGACCCUCAGCAGUUGUUACCCAGAUCUUCCAACUCCUCUGUCAGUGGCACCAAGAAAGAAGAUUCUACAGCAAAGAUUCAUGCUGUCACUCACUCAUCAACAGGAGAGCCGCUGGCUUAUAUCGCUCAGCCACCACUCAACCGCAAGACUUGUCCAAGCUCUGCUGUCAACUCAGAUCGAAGUAAAGGGAAUGGGAAAUCUAAUCACAGGACACAGUCUGCACAUAUCUCACCAGUGACUUCAACAUACUGUCUUUCCCCUCGACAGAAAGAACUACAAAAACAACUAGAAGAAAAGAGAGAAAAACUGAAAAGAGAGGAAGAGCGACGAAAAAUAGAAGAAGAGAAAGAAAAAAAGAGAGAGAAUGACAUAGUAUUUAAAGCGUGGUUGCAAAAGAAAAGAGAGCAGGUCUUAGAAAUGAGGAGAAUUCAGCGAGCAAAGGAAAUUGAAGACAUGAACAGUAGACAGGAAAACAGAGAUCCACAACAAGCUUUUCGAUUAUGGCUUAAAAAAAAGCACGAAGAGCAGAUGAAAGAAAGACAGACAGAAGAACUAAGAAAGCAAGAGGAAUGUUUAUUCUUCCUUAAAGGAACAGAAGGCCGGGAAAGGGCCUUUAAACAAUGGUUAAGAAGGAAACGGAUGGAAAAAAUGGCAGAGCAACAAGCUGUCAGAGAGAGAACUAGACAGCUCCGACUAGAAGCUAAGCGUUCUAAACAGUUACAGCACCACCUAUAUAUGUCAGAAGCCAAACCUUUUCGUUUUACUGAUCAUUAUAACUGAAAGUUUCUAUUAAAUAUUUCAGUGGGCAGCUGCUAUCAAAAUUUUGGAUAUGAUUUCUUAGGGUCUGUGUACUUUGGUUGUAUUCUAAAUUAUGGAAAUGGUAUUUAUCUUUUAUUGACAGUGAAUUUGUUUUUUUAAUACUAGAACAAAAUAAAUUUUUUUCUCACAGUGUUGUAA